GAAAGGCGCAUUGAUGCAGCCUGCGGCGGCCUCGGAGCGCGGCGGAGCCAGACGCUGACCACGUUCCUCUCCUCGGUCUCCUCCGCCUCCAGCUCCGCGCUGCCCGGCAGCCGGGAGCCAUGCGACCCCAGGGCCCCGCCGCCUCCCCGCAGCGGCUCCGCGGCCUCCUGCUGCUCCUGCUGCUGCAGCUGCCCGCGCCGUCGAGCGCCUCUGAGAUCCCCAAGGGGAAGCAAAAGGCGCAGCUCCGGCAGAGGGAGGUGGUGGACCUGUAUAAUGGAAUGUGCUUACAAGGGCCAGCAGGAGUGCCUGGUCGAGACGGGAGCCCUGGGGCCAAUGGCAUUCCGGGUACACCUGGGAUCCCAGGUCGGGAUGGAUUCAAAGGAGAAAAGGGGGAAUGUCUGAGGGAAAGCUUUGAGGAGUCCUGGACACCCAACUACAAGCAGUGUUCAUGGAGUUCAUUGAAUUAUGGCAUAGAUCUUGGGAAAAUUGCGGAGUGUACAUUUACAAAGAUGCGUUCAAAUAGUGCUCUAAGAGUUUUGUUCAGUGGCUCACUUCGGCUAAAAUGCAGAAAUGCAUGCUGUCAGCGUUGGUAUUUCACAUUCAAUGGAGCUGAAUGUUCAGGACCUCUUCCCAUUGAAGCUAUAAUUUAUUUGGACCAAGGAAGCCCUGAAAUGAAUUCAACAAUUAAUAUUCAUCGCACUUCUUCUGUGGAAGGACUUUGUGAAGGAAUUGGUGCUGGAUUAGUGGAUGUUGCUAUCUGGGUUGGUACUUGUUCAGAUUACCCAAAAGGAGAUGCUUCUACUGGAUGGAAUUCAGUUUCUCGCAUCAUUAUUGAAGAACUACCAAAAUAAAUGCUUUAAUUUUCAUUUGCUACCUCUUUUUUUAUUAUGCCUUGGAAUGGUUCACUUAAAUGACAUUUUAAAUAAGUUUAUGUAUACAUCUGAAUGAAAAGCAAAGCUAAAUAUGUUUACAGACCAAAGUGUGAUUUCACACUGUUUUUAAAUCUAGCAUUAUUCAUUUUGCUUCAAUCAAAAGUGGUUUCAAUAUUUUUUUUAGUUGGUUAGAAUACUUUCUUCAUAGUCACAUUCUCUCAACCUAUAAUUUGGAAUAUUGUUGUGGUCUUUUGUUUUUUCUCUUAGUAUAGCAUUUUUAAAAAAAUAUAAAAGCUACCAAUCUUUGUACAAUUUGUAAAUGUUAAGAAUUUUUUUUAUAUCUGUUAAAUAAAAAUUAUUUCCAACAA